UGAAGCCGCAGGAACAGAUGGCAUCGCCUGGGGAAAGUGGAGAGAGAGGAGGAUUCAGGAAGAGCCCUGGGAAAGCUUCAAGGACUAGGCAGAGAGAAACGAGCUGUGAAGGAGACGAGGAGUGCAGAACAGCAGGAAGCCUGACGGAGGGCGAGAUCAGCAGCAUCCACAUCUGCCAGAGGGCAAGCCAGGCCAGGAUUAGGGACGUUCCAUUGUGCGCCGUAAAAAUGAAACUUCAGUGACCUUGAUAAGCACAGAUUCAGUGGAUGGGUUGGGGGCAGAAGUGAGACAUGAAAAGGAGAUGAGGAUGGAGUGACAGCAAGUACAGCUCCUCGUUCAAAGGAUUUGGCUUUGAAGGGAAGAGAGAAAUGGAGUGAAUGAGGAAAGGAAAGAGGUUUUAAGAUGGAGAGAUUUGGACACACCUAAAUACUGAUGAGGAGGAGCAGAGAGAGAGAGAGACUGGAUCUGCAGGAUGAAGAGAGGUGGCAAGGAUAGAGGAACGUCCCUGUAGAGGAGAGAAGGCAAGGUCAAGGGGGUACGCAGAGGGACUGGCCUGGGCUAUGUGAGGGGCAGGGAGGAGGCAAACAGGGAAGCAGGCAACUUGGAGAGGAGGAAGCAGUUGAGGCCAGACCUGGAUGUGGUAGCUGAGUGGACUUUGAGAGCCAUAUGACAGGCCACACAUGCCUGAGGGAUGCAGGUCAGGGGCCGAAGAGCCACAGACAAACCCAAGGAGCUCCGAGCCGGGCUGAAAAAGGAAACGGUCCUUGGGAGUGGGACUUGGUGUGCAACUCCAACAAACUGAAGGAGAUGGCCCAGUCUAUCUUCAUGGCAGGUAUACUGAUUGGAGGGCUCGUGCUUGGAGACCUGUCUGACAGGUUUGGCCGCAGGCCCAUCCUGACCUGCAGCUACCUGCUGCUGGCAGCCAGCGGCUCCGGUGCAGCCUUCAGCCCCACCUUCCCCAUCUACAUGGUCUUCCGCUUCCUGUGUGGCUUUGGCAUCUCAGGCAUUACCCUGAGCACCGUCAUCUUGAAUGUGGAAUGGGUGCCUACCCGGAUGCGGGCCAUCAUGUCGACAGCACUCGGGUACUGCUACACCUUUGGCCAGUUCAUUCUGCCCGGCCUGGCCUACGCCAUCCCCCAGUGGCGUUGGCUGCAGUUAACUGUGUCCAUUCCCUUCUUCGUCUUCUUCCUAUCAUCCUGGUGGACACCAGAGUCCAUACGCUGGUUGGUCUUGUCUGGAAAGUCCUCGAAGGCCCUGAAGAUACUCCGGCGGGUGGCUGUCUUCAAUGGCAAGAAGGAAGAGGGAGAAAGGCUCAGCUUGGAGGAGCUCAAACUCAACCUGCAGAAGGAGAUCUCCUUGGCCAAGGCCAAGUACACCGCAAGUGACCUGUUCCGGAUACCCAUGCUGCGCCGCAUGACCUUCUGUCUUUCCCUGGCCUGGUUUGCUACCGGUUUUGCCUACUAUAGUUUGGCUAUGGGUGUGGAAGAAUUUGGAGUCAACCUCUACAUCCUCCAGAUCAUCUUUGGUGGGGUCGAUGUCCCAGCCAAGUUCAUCACCAUCCUCUCCUUAAGCUACCUGGGCCGGCAUACCACUCAGGCCGCUGCCCUGCUCCUGGCAGGAGGGGCCAUCUUGGCUCUCACCUUUGUGCCCUUGGACUUGCAGACCGUGAGGACAGUAUUGGCUGUGUUUGGGAAGGGAUGCCUAUCCAGCUCCUUCAGCUGCCUCUUCCUCUACACAAGUGAAUUAUACCCCACAGUCAUCAGGCAAACAGGUAUGGGCGUAAGUAACCUGUGGACCCGCGUGGGAAGCAUGGUGUCCCCGCUGGUGAAAAUCACGGGUGAGGUACAGCCCUUCAUCCCCAAUAUCAUCUACGGGAUCACCGCCCUCCUCGGGGGCAGUGCUGCCCUCUUCCUGCCUGAGACCCUGAAUCAGCCCUUGCCAGAGACUAUCGAAGACCUGGAAAACUGGUCCCUGCGGGCAAAGAAGCCAAAGCAGGAGCCAGAGGUGGAAAAGGCCUCCCAGAGGAUCCCUCUACAGCCUCACGGACCAGGCCUGGGCUCCAGCUGAGGACAACGGAACCCCCUUUCCCUGCCCUCCAGAGACUGAUCCUAGCCAGGCACCUUAGGAGUAUAGGGAGGCCCCAUAUAGGUCCAUCCUCCUAGGAUGAAGCCUUCUGAGAGCUUGGUGAAGGUGUCUCCAUCACCACCACCAGAGCCUCCUGCCCAGCCCUGGCCAGUUCAAAGGUUCAGCCAUCCCUGCCCUUGUUCUCCCUGCAACCCAGGCCCUGCCAUUCUUCUGUCUAGCCCUUCCCCACUGGCCACCUUCCCCCACUGUCCCGGUCCUCUUCCCCUGAGGUCCCCUGAUAUCCCCUGGCUCAGUCCUAACAAGACUGAGUCUUAACAAGAUGAGAAGUCCUCCCCUUCUUGCCUCCCACACUUUUCUUUGAUGGGAGGUUUCAAUAAACAGCGAUAAGAACUCUA